CAGGUGCGGCUGCUUCAGGUAGGGUGGUCAGGGAAGGAGGCGGCAUCUGAGCUUUGACCUCAAUUUCGAGAAUGAGCCAGGAAUGCAGAGAGGAUUUCAGGCAGAGGAAACCUUAGGGAGGCUGGCGGGUUAAAUCUGCAGGGGUGUGGCUGGCCGGAGGAAGUGAGGUGUGAGACAGUCACGUUGAUGGUGACAGCAGCAGUGACCGUAGCAGCCUAGAGGUGGCCGAAUGCUUACUCUAAUGGGCUGGCCCAUCCCUGAGUGUCUAGAGUUCCCAGCCCGCUUAAGGAAGGAAGGAAAACACAGGCAGCUCUAAGUGUACGACGAGGGAGGUCUCAUCGGCGGUGAGGAAGCCCAGGCGGGUCCCCUUCCCAGCUGAAAGGGGUUCGGAAUUUCACUCUGUCGCCAGGCUGGAAUGCAGUAGGGCAAUCUCGGCUCACUGCAACCUCCACCUCCCGAGUUCAAGUGAUGCUCCUGCUUCGGCCUCCUGAGUAGCUGGGACUACAGGUGAGUGCCACCACAUCCAGCUAAUUUUUGUAUUUUUAGUAGAGACAGGGUUUCACCAUGUUGGCCAGGCUGGUAUCAAUCUCCUGACCUCGUGAUCCAUCUGUCUCGGCCUCCCAAAGUGCUGGGAUUACAGGCGUGAGCCACCGUGCCCGGCCAUUGACUAAGGUCUUAAAAUAGCUCUUCCUGCCUGUAUAAUCUCCAUUAUGGCAGGGCUCAUAUAAGAAGAUGACAGUUCAUCUGAUGAGGAAGAAAACUUACUCCUAGUUAGAUUGGGUUGAAUUCUUCCCUGUUUCCAGCGGUGUCUGCUCCUGGCACCUCAGGCACAGUCAGGGGUAGGAGGUGGUGAUCAGAUACACUCGCUGUGAGCAGUGCAAGGGGAAGCAGGUGCCCAGAGGUGCAUCCCGGUUUGGUGGGGGUGACAAACAUGGACAGGUAAGUGCAGGAGUGUGUGCAAUACUCAAUCUAAGAAAGGUAGUUCAGGCAGAGUUCAGGGAAGAUAUCUCUGUGCAGGGCCAGACAUGGGGAUGAGAUUCUGAUAAUUUGGGAAUGAAUCAGGCCCCCAGCCCCUCCUCCCUCAGACUCAGCAGUCCAGGCACCCGGCCCUCCUCCCUCGGACCCAGAAGUCCAUGCUCCCAGCCCCUCCUCCCUUGGACCCAGGAGUCCAGGCCCCCAGCCCCUCCUCCCUCAGACCCAGGAGUCCAGGCCCCCAGCCGCCUUCUCCUGCAGGACCCCAGGAGCUUGGGUACCCACAGGCUACUAGAUCCUUGUUUCUGUGCAUGGAAAUUCUCAAAUUAUCUCCAAAAGUCUAUGAAGAAGGUAAACACACAUUUCCAGAUGAGGGAAUAGGCUGAUAUAGUUGAAAGACACACAGAGGGUCACAGUCUGGAAUUGACAGUGGUGGGAUUCGAACCUAUUUCACUCCAGAACUGCGUAGCGCCUUAUACGCUGCGGCAAGUGUGACGUCAUUCGAACAAACCAUAGGCCCCGCCCCCGGACUAGCCACGCCCACAGGCUCCUGAAACCACCAAUCCCAGCUGUGACAGCGCUCAGGACCGAUGCUCAUAGGUCCCGUCCCUAGGAUCCCCGCCCCCUCCGCCCGCGCCCCGCCCCUCGCAGCCCAGUUCCGGACGCGGGCCCAGCCGCGCCUGCGCCUCCGCUCGCCUGUGGCUGCGUCGCGCGCUCUUCCUCGGAGCUACCCAGGCGGCUGGUGUGCAGCAAGCUCCGCGCCGACCCCUGACGCCUGACGCCUGUCCCCGGCCCGGCAUGAGCCGCUACCUGCUGCCGCUGUCGGCGCUGGGCACGGUAGCAGGCGCCGCCGUGCUGCUCAAGGACUAUGUCACCGGUGGGGCUUGCCCCAGCAAGGCCACCAUCCCUGGGAAGACGGUCAUCGUGACGGGUGCCAACACAGGCAUCGGGAAGCAGACCGCCUUGGAACUGGCCAGGAGAGGAGGCAACAUCAUCCUGGCCUGCCGAGACAUGGAGAAGUGUGAGGCGGCAGCAAAGGACAUCCGCGGGGAGACCCUCAAUCACCAUGUCAACGCCCGGCACCUGGACUUGGCUUCCCUCAAGUCUAUCCGAGAGUUUGCAGCAAAGAUCAUUGAAGAGGAGGAGCGAGUGGACAUUCUAAUCAACAACGCGGGUGUGAUGCGGUGCCCCCACUGGACCACCGAGGACGGCUUCGAGAUGCAGUUUGGCGUUAACCACCUGGGUCACUUUCUCUUGACAAACUUGCUGCUGGACAAGCUGAAAGCCUCAGCCCCUUCGCGGAUCAUCAACCUCUCGUCCCUGGCCCAUGUUGCUGGGCACAUAGACUUUGACGACUUGAACUGGCAGACGAGGAAGUAUAACACCAAAGCCGCCUACUGCCAGAGCAAGCUCGCCAUCGUCCUCUUCACCAAGGAGCUGAGCCGGCGGCUGCAAGGCUCUGGUGUGACUGUCAACGCCCUGCACCCCGGCGUGGCCAGGACAGAGCUGGGCAGACACACGGGCAUCCAUGGCUCCACCUUCUCCAGCACCACACUCGGGCCCAUCUUCUGGCUGCUGGUCAAGAGCCCCGAGCUGGCCGCCCAGCCCAGCACAUACCUGGCCGUGGCGGAGGAACUGGCGGAUGUUUCCGGAAAGUACUUCGAUGGACUCAAACAGAAGGCCCCGGCCCCCGAGGCUGAGGAUGAGGAGGUGGCCCGGAGGCUUUGGGCUGAAAGUGCCCGCCUGGUGGGCUUAGAGGCUCCCUCUGUGAGGGAGCAGCCCCUCCCCAGAUAACCUCUGGAGCAGAUUUGAAAGCCAGGAUGGCGCCUCCAGACCGAGGACAGCUGUCCGCCAUGCCCGCAGCUUCCUGGCACUACCUGAGCCGGGAGACCCAGGACUGGCGGCCGCCAUGCCCGCAGUAGGUUCUAGGGGGCGGUGCUGGCCGCAGUGGACUGGCCUGCAGGUGAGCACUGCCCUGGGCUCUGGCUGGUUCCGUCUGCUCUGCUGCCAGCAGGGGAGAGGGGCCAUCUGAUGCUUCCCCUGGGAAUCUAAACUGGGAAUGGCCGAGGAGGAAGGGGCUCCGUGCACUUGCAGGCCACGUCAGGAGAGCCAGCGGUGCCUGUCGGGGAGGGUUCCAAGGUGCUCCGUGAAGAGCAUGGGCAAGUUGUCUGACACUUGGUGGAUUCUUGGGUCCCUGUGGGACCUUGUGCAUGCAUGGUCCUCUCUGAGCCUUGGUUUCUUCAGCAGUGAGAUGCUCAGAAUAACUGCUGUCUCCCAUGAUGGUGUGGUACAGCGAGCUGUUGUCUGGCUAUGGCAUGGCUGUGCCGGGGGUGUUUGCUGAGGGCUUCCUGUGCCAGAGCCCAGCCAGAGAGCAGGUGCAGGUGUCAUCCUGAGUUCAGGCUCUGCACGGCAUGGAGUGGGAACCCCACCAGCUGCUGCUACAGGACCUGGGAUUGCCUGGGACUCCCACCUUCCUAUCAAUUCUCAUGGUAGUCCAAACUGCAGACUCUCAAACUUGCUCAUUUAAAAGAAAAAAAAAAGAAGAAAAUGUA